GACAUUCCAUAUACAAGAUGGCCGCAGUCGGCAAGGAGAGACGUCGCUGAGGGGCUUGCCUGAAGCGAGGGGUGAGUGACCCACCGACUGAGGGCAGCGCCGCCCACCUCCCGCGUAUCUGGAGGUCGGAGUAGGUUAUGGCCAACCGCCGCUAUCCACUGGCGGAGUCUCUCUUUCCGGAUUCUGCCUCCCUCCGCUAACCUCCGCAUGGAGCUUUUGGAGAGUGUCUUUAUUCUGAGUGAAAGAAAAGGAAGAGGAUGAAAAAGCAAGAACAGUUUAAAGGAGCUCCUUCUCUCAUGGACCACUUCCAUCCACCCACUCCCCAAAUCACAAGAUGCACAUUUGGUUUACAUCAGUGAAUUCAGUGAUUUGUGCAGAUGUGAAUUAACCCAAUCCCAUGACUUGUCUAAGUGAAAGUGCCUACAUGGAAUAAACUGAAAAGGGGUGCUGGAUGGAAGAGAUGGUUAGUUUUAGAACAUAAAUCUUUGUCAAGAUUAAGACAGGCCCAGGUUUUGCUGAAGAAUGGAAUCUGGACCAGCGUUAGAGGACCUGUAUGUCUAGUGAAGAAAAACCAGAAGAAAGAUUCUAACAUUUUCAGAGAACCUUUUGGAAAGAACAAGCCUACUUCAAUAAAUGAAGGAGAAUAAAGAAAAUUCAAGCCCUUCAGUAACUUCAGCAAACCUGGACCACACAAAGCCAUGUUGGUACUGGGAUAAGAAAGACUUGGCUCAUACACCCUCACAACUUGAAGGACUUGAUCCAGCCACCGAGGCCCGGUACCGCCGAGAGGGCGCUCGGUUCAUCUUUGAUGUGGGCACACGUUUGGGGCUACACUAUGAUACCCUGGCAACUGGAAUAAUUUAUUUUCAUCGCUUCUAUAUGUUUCAUUCCUUCAAGCAAUUCCCAAGAUAUGUGACAGGAGCCUGUUGCCUCUUUCUGGCUGGGAAAGUAGAAGAAACACCAAAAAAAUGUAAAGAUAUCAUCAAAACAGCUCGUAGUUUAUUAAAUGAUGUACAAUUUGGCCAGUUUGGAGAUGACCCAAAGGAGGAAGUAAUGGUUCUGGAGAGAAUCUUACUGCAGACCAUCAAGUUUGAUUUACAGGUAGAACAUCCAUACCAGUUCCUACUAAAAUAUGCAAAGCAACUCAAAGGUGAUAAAAACAAAAUUCAAAAGUUGGUUCAAAUGGCAUGGACAUUUGUAAAUGACAGUCUCUGCACCACCUUGUCACUGCAGUGGGAACCAGAGAUCAUAGCAGUAGCAGUGAUGUAUCUCGCAGGACGUUUGUGCAAAUUUGAAAUACAAGAAUGGACCUCCAAACCCAUGUAUAGGAGAUGGUGGGAGCAGUUUGUUCAAGAUGUCCCGGUCGACGUUUUGGAAGACAUCUGCCACCAAAUCCUGGAUCUUUACUCACAAGGAAAACAACAGAUGCCUCAUCACACCCCCCAUCAGCUGCAACAGCCCCCAUCUCUUCAGCCUACACCACAAGUGCCGCAAGUACAGCAGUCACAGCCGUCUCAAAGCUCCGAACCAUCCCAGCCCCAGCAGAAGGACCCCCAGCAACCAGCCCAGCAGCAGCAGCCAGCCCAACAGCCCAAGAAACCCUCUCCGCAGCCCAGUUCUCCCCGACAGGUUAAGCGAGCCGUGGUUGUUUCUCCCAAAGAAGAGAACAAAGCAGCAGAACCACCACCACCUAAAAUCCCCAAAAUUGAGACCACUCAUCCACCGUUGCCUCCAGCCCACCCACCUCCAGACCGGAAGCCUCCCCUCGCUGCUGCCUUAGGUGAGGCUGAGCCGCCGGGCCCUGUGGAUGCCACUGACCUCCCCAAAGUCCAGAUUCCCCCUCCGGCCCACCCGGCCCCUGUGCACCAGCCACCGCCGCUGCCACACCGGCCCCCGCCCCCACCCCCCUCCAGCUACAUGACCGGGAUGUCCACCACCAGCUCCUACAUGUCUGGAGAGGGCUACCAGAGCCUGCAGUCCAUGAUGAAGACCGAGGGACCCUCCUACGGUGCCCUGCCCCCCGCCUACGGCCCACCUGCACACCUGCCCUACCACCCCCAUGUCUACCCGCCCAACCCGCCCCCGCCACCUGUGCCUCCUCCCCCAGCCUCCUUCCCCCCACCUGCCAUCCCACCCCCUACUCCUGGCUACCCCCCACCCCCACCCACCUACAACCCCAACUUCCCACCCCCACCCCCACGCCUCCCGCCUACCCACGCAGUCCCCCCUCAUCCUCCUCCAGGGUUGGGCCUGCCGCCAGCCAGCUACCCACCUCCUGCCGUCCCCCCUGGAGGACAGCCUCCUGUGCCCCCGCCCAUUCCCCCACCCGGCAUGCCUCCAGUUGGGGGGCUGGGGCGGGCAGCCUGGAUGAGAUAACGUGAGCCUUUUUUCCCUCUUUGUUUUUUUAACAAGAUUUUCUAAUCGACUUGCAGAGUAGUUGAAGUGGGUAAGCAGCAGGGUACCUUGUAUAAUGCACGACAGUUGCAGUAUGGGAAGAAUGGACCGGGCCCCUGGGAUAAAAUCAGAGUGGUCCUCACACCUAGAGGACGGGGACAACCAGCUUUCAGAGUAGCCUCAUCAGUGCCCUUGCAGUCUGACUGUGUACACUUGGUUCAGCUAAUGUCUGAGAGUCCUGCACUGGGUUACUUUAUACUAGUGAGGACGUUAACCAGCCAUAUUGGCUCAAUAAAUAGCUUCGGUAAGGAGUUAAUUUCCUUCUAGAAAUCAGUGCCUAUUUUUCCUGGAAACUCAAUUUUAAAUAGUCCAAUUCCAUCUGAAGCCAAGCUGUUGUCAUUUUCAUUCGGUGACAUUCUCUCCCAUGACACCCAGAAGGGGCAGAAGAACCACAUUUUUCAUUUAUAGAUGUUUGCAUCCUUUGUAUUAAAAUUAUUUUGAAGGGGUUGCCUCAUUGGAUGGCUUUUUUUUUUUCCUCCAGGGAGAAGGGGAGAAAUGUACUUGGAAAUUAAUGUAUGUUUACAUCUCUUUGCAAAUUCCUGUACAUAGAGAUAUAUUUUUUAAGUGUGAAUGUAACAACAUACUGUGAAUUCCAUCUUGGUUACAAAUGAGACUCCUUCAGUCAGUUAUCCAAAUAAAAGCAGUUCUGAAACUAUCCCUUUCUUUGUUAUGGGUGGAAGGUGGGGCUCCAGGCCUUCGCAGUCUGUGGCUUAUAAAAUGUGCAGAGGCCCUCCUUCCAGACCCUGGGGACGCGGGAGAGGCCUGGCUGCAGCUCACAGCAGCCACAGCCAACCCCACUGCCUCCCAAGGCACUCUGGGUGGAUCCGCACAGCUGCCUGCCAAGCCAGCCUGCCCCCAUCCUGUGCCUGCCUUGGUUUCCUUUGGAGGACCUGGUUGAGUUCCAAACCAGUUUGAAACUUUGAAGCCUUGCUGCGUAGAACGCACACAGGAACCCGGGGGCUUGGAUUUGAAACCCUUUCCACUUCUGGCCUGUGAUGAGACAGAGGCAGCUGGAGGAGCAGCGGCCUCACUGUCCACCUUGAGGGGCCACGGCUCUGUCUGUGGAAGGGGCCCCGACUGAGCCCCCAUCUGCGGUGCUUGAGGGGCCUUGGCCCUGUCUCUGCCUGCUGACCCUGCCACCCACGACAGAAACAAGCACUGAGCACCCAGCCAGGAGGCUCACAAAGAGGCCUUUAUUUAUCUAGCUCAAAGUAGACACUAUCACAAUCUUGUUUGUUACUCCUUUUACUAAAAUAGUUCAAAUCAAUGUUUUUACCACACUAUCAAAAAGUUCUAUUUCUUCUUGUCUCCCCACGUCAGAGUGGUUGAAUAGAAGGUAGAAACAGGCCGGGAGUCCACGGGCUCCCAGCUCUAAACGGCGCCAGGGCAGGAAGGGGUGGCUCCAGGUCUCACUGUGGCACCUUCUACAGAAAAUAGACGUAGCUGCCGGGCCCGGGGACAGAAACCAGACGUUCCAGUCCAUCUCCAAAAAGCAGCACAAAUACUUUGCCCCACAGUAUGAAAAAUAUACACCUCUACCGCUCUGCAGUCAUGCAUUUAGUUUUAAGAAAAAAAAAAAA